GCCACAAACGCUGAGCCCAGGUGGGAGAGGUCUGGCCUAUCCGCGCCUGGCAGCUGUCGGAACUCCGGAGACCACAAAGGGGUUUAUGGUUUACCCCCUCCACGGAAGGUCGGUCUGAUCGCAGCUGCGGGUCGGGGAGAGGGACCGGGGGUCCCCCAGUCAGUAGGCCUCAGAACACCUCUUCAGUGCCGGGGCACCAGACAGCGGAUUUUGCAUUCGACUCUCCCCAAAGUGUGCCGAACAGGUUGGAAGCAAAGGCUCCGGUUUAAGCUCUGGGCUUGGGGAUAAAAUACACUUUUUAAGGACCCAAGUUCCUCGGCAACGACUCCAGACUGGGAAGACCUUUCCAUUUUCAGGAUCGACGCUUCACGUUGAGGGGAGGGCAUUCAGGACGCCCUCUUAAGGCUUCUCCCAACCCAUGGCGCUACCAGGCUCCUCACAGGACCAGGCCUGGAGCCUGGAGCCUCCGGCUGCCACGGCUGCUGCCUCCUCAUCUUCGGGACCCCAGGAGCGGGAGGGCGCUGGGAGCCCCGCGGCCCCCGGGACGCUGCCCCUGGAGAAGGUGAAGCGGCCGAUGAACGCGUUCAUGGUGUGGAGCUCCGCUCAGCGCCGCCAGAUGGCGCAGCAGAACCCCAAGAUGCACAACUCCGAGAUCUCCAAGCGCCUGGGCGCGCAGUGGAAGCUGCUGGACGAGGACGAGAAGCGGCCCUUCGUGGAGGAGGCCAAGCGGCUCCGCGCCCGACACCUGCGCGACUACCCCGACUACAAGUACCGGCCUCGGCGCAAGGCCAAGAGCUCGGGCGCCGGACCUUCCCGCUGCGGACAGGGAAGAGGCAACCUGGCCAGCGGCGGCCCGCUCUGGGGGCCGGGGUACGCGACCACCCAACCGAGCAGAGGCUUUGGGUACAGACCCCCCAGCUACUCGACAGCCUACCUGCCUGGCAGCUAUGGCUCUUCCCACUGCAAACUGGAAGCCCCCUCACCGUGCUCCCUCCCUCAGAGUGACCCUAGGCUCCAGGGGGAACUGCUGCCCACCUAUACCCACUACCUGCCCCCUGGCUCUCCCACUCCAUACAACCCUCCCCUUGCUGGUGCCCCCAUGCCCCUAACCCACCUCUAACCCUCAUGGACGCAGACCUCACGGGACGGGCCUCAUCCUCCUUUUUUAAUCCAGCAGCAUCCCCUACCCCAGGCUGUCAACCCUUUCUCCUGUUGGACUACAGUUCAGAGGCAGCCUGCAGUCCUCCCAUGAUAGCCAGGGAGAGCCGCACAACAUACAAUUAUAUUUUUGGUAGUAUUAAACAGUUUUGUAUUAUUCAA